GUGGGUGACGAGUGGUGGCCGAAGCAGGGGGACAGCAAGGGACGCUCAGGCGGGGACCAUGGCGGACGGCGGCUCGGAGCGGGCUGACGGGCGCAUCGUCAAGAUGGAGGUGGACUACAGCGCCACGGUGGAUCAGCGCCUACCCGAGUGUGCGAAGCUAGCCAAGGCAUGCCUUUAUAGGUAUUGAUUUAAAUCUUACACCAACCCUGUGGAUUGGUACAAUUAUUGUGCCCACUUCGCUGAAGAGAAAAUUGAGAGUCAGAGAGCUUGUGUUUUACUCAAGGUUGUGUAACAAAUCAUUGAAAGAUUGGAUUCAUUCAGGAAUUAAAGGAGGUGCAAACAGAACUUAUACUCAACAUUGAUGUUGAACAAACUCAUUAGUCGCUUACAUCAUUUACAAGGAUUAUUUUAAUGAGGAAAAUGAGUCACUGAAGUCACAUGUUCUAACAGGAAGGAAGACUUCAAGAAGUCAUUGAAACCCUUCUCUCUCUGGAAAAGCAGACUCGUACUGCUUCCGAUAUGGUAUCGACAUCCCGUAUCUUAGUUGCAGUAGUGAAGAUGUGCUAUGAGGCUAAAGAAUGGGAUUUACUUAAUGAAAAUAUUAUGCUUUUGUCCAAAAGGCGGAGUCAGUUAAAACAAGCUGUUGCCAAAAUGGUUCAACAGUGCUGUACUUAUGUUGAGGAAAUCACAGACCUUCCUAUCAAACUUCGAUUAAUUGAUACUCUACGAAUGGUUACCGAAGGCAAGAUUUAUGUUGAAAUUGAGCGUGCGCGACUGACUAAAACAUUAGCAACUAUAAAAGAACAAAAUGGUGAUGUGAAAGAGGCAGCCUCCAUUUUACAGGAGUUACAGGUGGAAACCUACGGGUCAAUGGAAAAGAAAGAGCGAGUGGAAUUUAUUUUGGAGCAAAUGAGGCUCUGCCUAGCUGUGAAGGAUUACAUUCGAACACAAAUCAUCAGCAAGAAAAUUAACACCAAAUUUUUCCAGGAAGAAAAUACAGAGAAAUUAAAGUUGAAGUACUAUAAUUUAAUGAUUCAGCUGGAUCAACAUGAGGGAUCCUAUUUGUCUAUUUGUAAGCACUACAGAGCAAUAUAUGAUACUCCCUGUAUACAGGCAGAAAGUGAAAAAUGGCAGCAGGCUCUGAAGAGUGUUGUACUCUAUGUUAUCCUGGCUCCUUUUGACAAUGAACAGUCAGAUUUGGUUCACCGAAUAAGUGGUGACAAGAAGUUAGAAGAAAUUCCCAAAUACAAGGAUCUUUUAAAGCUUUUUACCACAAUGGAGUUGAUGCGUUGGUCCACACUUGUUGAGGACUAUGGAAUGGAAUUAAGAAAAGGUUCCCUUGAGAGUCCUGCAACGGAUGUUUUUGGUUCUACAGAGGAAGGUGAAAAAAGGUGGAAAGACUUGAAGAACAGAGUUGUUGAACAUAAUAUUAGAAUAAUGGCCAAGUAUUAUACUCGGAUAACAAUGAAAAGGAUGGCACAGCUUCUGGAUCUAUCUGUUGAUGAGUCCGAAGCCUUUCUCUCAAAUCUAGUAGUUAACAAGACCAUCUUUGCUAAAGUAGACAGAUUAGCAGGAAUUAUCAACUUCCAGAGACCCAAGGAUCCAAAUAAUUUAUUAAAUGACUGGUCUCAGAAACUGAACUCAUUAAUGUCUCUGGUUAACAAAACUACGCAUCUCAUAGCCAAAGAGGAGAUGAUACAUAAUCUACAAUAAGGGUCUUAGUGCUUUAGAAAAAAGUUAAAAUUGGAAGUCAUUAAAAAAAGACUGUUAUAAUGGUGUAUAUGUUGGGGUUUUUUUUCUAAGCUUCUUUGUCUUAAAUUUUAAAAUAGUGAAUAUGUUUGAGACUCCCUUUGACCUUUCAGUUCCCCAAGUUCAUUGUUAACUUUGCAUUUGCAAUUGGUGCAAAAAUACAGAUUUCUGUCGUCUGAAUACACAAAAAGUUGUGUCAUAACUUACCCAGAUAUGUUUUUCUAUCAUUUGAAACCUUUUUAGCUACUGUUUGUUUUCAUUCAACUAACAAACAUAUUCCAAUAAUAAAAGCAGUAUAUACAUAUUUCCUUUCUACAGUUACCUCUGAUUCUCAACAUUUUGUGGGGUAGUGAUUUGGCAAGUGUUUUUUAAAUAAAACAAAUCUCAUUGUAAAGCUAUCAGUCAUUUAGUAGAAUAGAAAAGCAACAUAGAGCAUACAAGAACAUUUGGGAUAGAGUUGUGAUUUGUGAAGAAUUUGUACUUUGAUAUUGUGGCGGAAAGUCUAGACUGAGUGUGUAUGCUGGUAAACUGUAGACUUUUUUUUUUUUUUUUUUGAGUCCGGCUGGUUCCAAUCACAGUAGCUUGAUUGCUUUCAGCCCUCAUCCUCUCACUUGAUCAGUUGUUCAACAGAAUCAGCUGACAUAAUUGACACAGUUUAUUGGGUGUUAAGUCCGCUCUAUAGGGAUAGUGACUACUUUUUUUUUUUUUUUUUUUUUGCUCUUCUUCCUCUCCCCUUUCUUUAUAUGGGUUUAAAUUUAACAUAAAGUUGUUUUUAUAAGGCUUAUUUGUGGCUUUAACUUGUAAGUCUGAUUACAUCAUUAUUGUUCCAAAUUCAUUAUCUCUGUAGGAACUUUUAGUUCCAUUAUAUGAACACUGGAUAACCUAAUUUUUUUUAAUGCUUUAAAAAAAUGGCAAAAAGACGUCAGGCCACCCUCAUAGUAAGUGGUGUAGUAUUAAAAUAUUUUCACGGAAUUAAAAGUAGCUUGCUGUCAAAGAAACACCUGAGAUGAAUUGGUGUGAACGAAUUUUGCAAGUUUAAUUUGAUUUAUUUCAGAGAAAAUAGAAAAAACAAUGUUAGAAGGUUAUUUAAAAUGAUACUUAAAUAAAGAAAGUGUGAGGUCUACUUUAAAAAAAUUCAAAUGAAGAGAAAAAGAAAAACAGCAUUCUAGAAAUGGCAUUUCUCCUAAUUAAUUUUCCACUUAAUGGAAGAUUAUCAAUUGUCCUAUUUUAUGAUCCCAGGACUGAAGACAGUUGUGGGAUAUCUGUCAUAUUUAUCCUGUGAGUCAUUGUGAAUAAUGACAUACAGUACUGAAGUAAUCUGAUUUUAUUCUUUGGAAAUUCAAUGCAUUGGUCACACUAAUAACAUCAACAUCUGCUAUCACUUAUCUUUUUAAAACUAACCAAAAAAGGCCGGGUGCAGUGGAUCCCAGCACUUUGGGAGGCCAAGGCGGGUGGAUCAUCUAAGGUCAGGAUUUCGAGACUAGCCUGGCCAACAUGGCAAAACCCUGUCUCUACUAAAAAAAAUACAAAAAUUUGCCGGGCGUGGUGGCGUGUGCCUGUAGUCCCAGUUACUUGGGAGGCUGAGGUGGGAGAAUUCCUUGAAGCCAGGAGGCGGAGGUUGCAGUGAGCCAAGAUCACACCAUUGCACUCCAGCCUGGGUGACAGAGUGAGACUCCGUCUCAAAAAAAAAAAAACAAAACUGGAAAGUUCAGAAACAGAAGUUCACACUAACAGAGUAUGGUUUUAAUUUUCCUUUGAAUGAAAAGGAUAGAAGAUAAAAUUGUGUAUUGUUAACAUGUAAAUAAAAUUGGAGCUAAUUUGAAACUAGCUUCUCAAUAACUUCAUCUUUCUAGAGACUCAUUACCUGUGGGCUUGUCAAACCUGGACUAUUUGGCCAAAUAGGUUGCUAUAGAGAUUGCAAGUGUUCCUCCUCUUUAUUUUUUUCAUAUUUUUUGAGACGGAGUUUCACUCUUGUUGCCCAGGCUGGAUUGCAGUGUCACGAUCUCGGCUCACUGCAACCUUUGCCUCCCAUAUUCAAGCAGUUCUCCUGCCUCAACCUCCCAAGUAGCUGGGAUUAUAGGCGCCUGCCACCACACCUAGCUAAUUUUUGUGUUUUUAGUAGAGAUGGUUUCAUCAUGUUGGCCGGGCUGGUCUCAAACUCCUGACCUCAGGUGAUCCACCCGCCUUGGCUGCCCAAAGUGCUGGGAUUACAGGCAUGAGCCACUGCACCCAACUCCUCUUUCGUCUUUCUUUAACACACACUAGGCUCUUUGUGUAUUAUGAUUCAGUGCUAUUUGUAACUGUGUCCCAGUGACCAAAUUGCACUCGACUCGAUCAGCUGUUCAUCCAUUUCGUGUUUUUUCCUGUCAAACAUUAAUCCAGCAAAUAUAUGAGGUAUUUACCAAUUUAUUUUCUUAGUAUUACAAAAUAAUUCAUUAGCAUAAAGUACAAUAGUGAAAUAUUUGAGUUGUUCGGAACCUCAAUUAAUCCUGUUUUACAUUUCAGACCUAAAGCUGGCAAUCAGGAGAAGAAGCACUUUGUUUUAAAUGUGGAGAAGAUAACACUUGAUUCCAUUUCAUUGUCAUUAGUGUAUUAACCAGCAGGAGAGGUGAUGAGCCAUUUUUCAAAUGAAAUACCUUUUAUUUCCAUAUAAUUUUUUUAUUUUAGAGUUCAAUAGCUGUUUCUAUGAUUAUCCUCAAUUUCCAUAUGUUACUGAAUCUGAAAAACAUCUUUAAAAUUCAAACAGUUCCAUUUUCUCUCUUGUAAGUGUUAAAUGUGAUAAAAGUACAUAUUUUAAAUUGUUUUCAGCUCUUGGAUAUAGCAGCAAUAAAAACACUAAUUUGUGGGUAUUUAAGAAAACCUGGAGAAUAAACUCAUACUUUAAAAGAUCA